ACUCGCAGCUGGGCACCCGAGCUUUCUUCGGGGUCGAGGAGGGUGGCUGGCUCUUGGCGGGGAGCAGGAGAGGGUAGGUGCCAAACCGAGACCCUGGCGGGGUCCCUUCGGGUUUGGGCAGGUCGAUGGGCAAGGGGGUGCCCACUAGUGAGGAGGGACACCCACCAAUUCCAGGCGAUGCUCCCCUGUGCCGCUCAGCAAAGCUAGGCCCGGGGAUCCUGCUCUUCUCCGGUCUGGUUAAGCCAGCAACCUCUGACACUUAGGAGAAAGUUAGUAACGUGUUACGAGUCAGUUUUUAGUGAAAAAACAUUGAGCUAGGAGCCAAGACCCAUCUCUUCACUAUUUUGGUAUUGUGCAAGUCAUCUUACCUCUCUGGAUCUCAGUUGUCUCAUCUGUAAAAAGGAGAUAAAAAUUAUUUACCUGCCUGAACGUCCGUAUCUCUCUUAUGAAAGAAGAGGGUGAUAAAGGAAAGGAGAAGGCCAUUCUUACUGACCUGAUAGUGGAAGAAAAGUAGAUGAGGUGGAGGACCAUCCUGCUACAGUAUUGCUUUCUCUUGAUUACAUGUUUACUUACUGCUCUUGAAGCUGUGCCUAUUGACAUAGACAAGACAAAAGUACAAAAUAUUCACCCUGUGGAAAGUGCGAAGAUAGAACCACCAGAUACUGGACUUUAUUAUGAUGAAUAUCUCAAGCAAGUGAUUGAUGUGCUGGAAACAGAUAAACACUUCAGAGAAAAGCUCCAGAAAGCAGACAUAGAGGAAAUAAAGAGUGGGAGGCUAAGCAAAGAACUGGAUUUAGUAAGUCACCAUGUGAGGACAAAACUUGAUGAACUGAAAAGGCAAGAAGUAGGAAGGUUAAGAAUGUUAAUUAAAGCUAAGUUGGAUUCCCUUCAAGAUAUAGGCAUGGACCACCAAGCUCUUCUAAAACAAUUUGAUCACCUAAACCACCUGAAUCCUGACAAGUUUGAAUCCACAGAUUUAGAUAUGCUAAUCAAAGCGGCAACAAGUGAUCUGGAACACUAUGACAAGACUCGUCAUGAAGAAUUUAAAAAAUAUGAAAUGAUGAAGGAACAUGAAAGGAGAGAAUAUUUAAAAACAUUGAAUGAAGAAAAGAGAAAAGAAGAAGAGUCUAAAUUUGAAGAAAUGAAGAAAAAGCAUGAAAAUCACCCUAAAGUUAAUCACCCAGGAAGCAAAGAUCAACUAAAAGAGGUAUGGGAAGAGACUGAUGGAUUGGAUCCUAAUGACUUUGACCCCAAGACAUUUUUCAAAUUACAUGAUGUCAAUAGUGAUGGAUUCCUGGAUGAACAAGAAUUAGAAGCCCUAUUUACUAAAGAGUUGGAGAAAGUAUAUGACCCUAAAAAUGAAGAGGAUGAUAUGGUAGAAAUGGAAGAAGAAAGGCUUAGAAUGAGGGAACAUGUAAUGAAUGAGGUUGAUACUAACAAAGACAGAUUGGUGACUCUGGAGGAGUUUUUGAAAGCCACAGAAAAAAAAGAAUUCUUGGAGCCAGAUAGCUGGGAGACAUUAGAUCAGCAACAGUUCUUCACAGAGGAAGAACUAAAAGAAUAUGAAAAUAUUAUUGCUUUACAAGAAAAUGAACUUAAGAAGAAGGCAGAUGAGCUUCAGAAACAAAAAGAAGAGCUACAACGUCAGCAUGAUCAACUGGAGGCUCAGAAGCUGGAAUAUCAUCAGGUCAUACAGCAGAUGGAACAAAAAAAAUUACAACAAGGAAUUCCUCCAUCAGGGCCAGCUGGAGAAUUGAAGUUUGAGCCACACAUUUAAAGUCUGAAGUCCACCAGAACUUGGAAGAAAGCUGUUAACUCAACAUCUAUUUCAUCUUUUUAGCUCCCUUCCUUUUUCUCUGCUCAAUAAAUAUUUUAAAAGCAUAUUUGAAAUAAAGGGAGAUACUUUUUAAAUGAAAACACUUUUUUUGGGACACAGAUAUUAAAGGAUUGAAGUUUAUCAGAACCAGGAAGAAAACAAACUCACUGUCUGCUCUCUGCUCUCACAUUCACACGGCUCUUUUAUUUAUUUUUUUGUUCUCCUUUAAUGAUUUAAUUAAGUGGCUUUAUGCCAUAAUUUAGUGAAACUAUUAGGAACUAUUUAAGUGAGAAAACUCUGCCUCUUGCUUUUAAAUUAGAUUGCUCUCACUUACUCGUAAACAUAGGUAUUCUUUUAUGGGUGCUUAUCAUUCCUUCUUUCAAUAAAUGUCUGUUUGAUAUUAACAAUUCUGGAAAGGCCACAGUAUUUCCCUGUGUUUCCUGGUAACGUUUUUCUAGUUUUGGCAACCUCAACUGCUAGAAAUUCUUCACCUGAAUCACUUUUGCUACCACUUCAGGUCAUUUUUCAUUCUUUUUUAUUUUGCUCUAUACUUUAUCAUUUAAGAUUAGGUUAUGUUACAUAUAACAGAAAAAACAAAGAUAACAGUGGUUUAAACUAAAUAGGAGUUUUUCUUCUUACAUAAGUCUAGAAGUAGGUGGUGUCCAGGUUCCUAUCUUUCUGCUCUGCUAUCCUCAGUGCAUGAUUUUUAUCCUCAGAUUACCUCACUCUCACUGUUCAAGUUUGCUCCUGGAG